ACAGGGCUCCCAGCAAUAGAGCAGUCCCACUCUCCCAGAUGAGCUGGAGAAGUAGCUACCUCUCCCAGACAGAGUUGGGGUCAAAUUCAUGCACAUCCAAUUCCCAUCAAAGCCUACUCUUCCCAGGGCUUGCUGGGAGGGAAGGAUAACUGCAGGCUCCCCUGGGAUGCCCCCAGGUGAGGGAAGUUCACAGAGUUUGAGACAGAGGUGAAUGGACAGGUGUGCUUCUUAGGGAAGCAGUCGAGAGGUGGCAAGAAGUUGGCAGCUGCCCUCAAGAGGGUCCUGGCACCAUGGACAAUGACAAGCCUCUUCAGCCUGAGACAGAAGAUGAGAUUGAAAUUGAGCCAGUACGACAGAGCAGCGAUAAAAUGCUCUACUGUGAGGCCGAAUCCCCGCCGACUGUUGAAAAAGUGAAACCAGCCCGGGAGAAUUCGGAAACAGACCUGGAGAUUGAAGAUGAUGAGAAAUUUUUCACCACUGGACAAAAGGAGCUGUACCUGGAGGCCUGCAAGCUGAUGGGUGUAGUGCCUGUCUCCUACUUCAUUCGGAACAUGGAGGAGUCCUACGUGAACCUCAACCACCACGGCCUGGGCCCCAGGGGUACCAAGGCUAUUGCUAUAGCCCUGGUGUCCAACAUGGCUGUUACCAAACUGGAGCUGGAAGACAAUUGCAUCAUGGAGGAGGGCGUCUUGAGCCUGGUGGAGAUGCUACAAGAGAACUACUACCUCCAGGAGAUGAAUAUUUCCAACAAUCACCUUGGUUUGGAGGGGGCCAGAAUCAUCUCAGAUUUCUUUGAGAGAAACAGUUCUUCUAUCUGGAGCCUUGAGCUUUCAGGAAAUGACUUCAAGGAAGACUCCGCAGCACUGCUCUGCCAAGCCCUGUCGACCAAUUACCAAAUUAAAAAGCUGGAUCUCAGUCACAACCAAUUCUCUGAUGUAGGAGGGGAGCACCUGGGCCAGAUGCUGGCCAUCAACGUGGGGCUCACGUCACUGGAUCUGAGCUGGAAUAACUUCCACACAAGGGGAGCUGUGGCCUUGUGCAAUGGUCUCCGGGGUAAUGUGACCCUGACAAAGCUGGAUCUCUCCAUGAAUGGCUUUGGGAAUGAGGUGGCUCUGGCCCUAGGGGAAGUCCUCCGACUCAACCGCUGCCUGGUCUACCUGGAUAUCGGUGGCAAUGACAUCGGCAAUGAAGGGGCCUCCAAAAUCAGCAAAGGACUGGAAUCCAAUGAAAGCCUCAGAGUUCUGAAGCUUUUCCUGAAUCCCAUAAAUAUGGAUGGGGCUAUUUUACUUAUCCUGGCUAUCAAGAGGAACCCCAAAUCCAGGAUGGAAGAGCUUGAUAUUUCCAACGUGCUGGUGUCCGAGCAGUUCAUGAAAACGUUGGACGGAGUGUAUGCCGUUCACCCGCAGCUGGACGUGGUAUUCAAGGCAGUACAAGGCCUCUCUCCCAAGAAAACCAUCUUCUUGUUGACAAACCCCAUGAAACUGAUCCAGAGCUAUGCAGACCAACACAAAAUCACGAUCGUGGACUUCUUCAAGAGCUUGAACCCCACUGGGACAAUGAAGAUGUCUGUGGAUGAGUUCCAGAAAGUGAUGAUAGAGCAAAACAAGGUCCCCCUGAACCAGUACCAGGUCAGGGAGGUGAUAAAGAAGCUCGAUGAGAAGACAGGCAUGGUGAACUUCAGGUCAGCCCAGGCCCCGCGACGAUCCCCGUUCUCUGCAAGGGGCCCUGGCUGGGCUGAUUUUCUUGAACACGAUGAAGCCAUAGCAACAAGUCUGGUCUAGAAAGAAGUCUCGGCGAGAGGAGUCCUCGCAAGUCGGAUGGUGGCAGGGAGGAGAGCAAGAGGUGGCUGAAAUCUCGAUGGACAGAUGCUGUGGCAGGGGCUGGGCACAAGCAAAUAAAGUCUGGCUUGGUUCUGGGUG